AUGGAGGAUAAGGGUGGUGAGAAUAUGCCAGGGAGAAAAAAGGAAGUGACUGACGGCAUUAUAAGAAAUAAAAUGUUCAUAAGCGCCUCUAAUUUCACCGACCCUGGCAAACUGCAGGAGACAUUCAGUCCACGCCACAUAAAAACUAUUAAAGUGGGAUCGCCGCAGUUGAAAAGCCCGAUCAGUGCCUGGAGAUUAGAACGCGAGCCUUUAAAGUACACACGCACCCGGCACCGGGAAAGCCCAGGCGCCUGUGACCCUCCGAAGGACUCUGGUGUCGAAGUUUCCCCUUCGCGCUGUGCCUCUGGUGAAAACAGGACAUCCCCUUCGGCCACCCCACAACAAAUAGCGUACACAAGCGGGGGAGAAGCGGGGCGGAGGGAGAAGCCGGCUCCGAGGGGGAGGAGGAAAGGAGAGGAGCCAAAACUCCGGACUGCGACAGGGGGGAAAGGAGAAGAAAAGAAAAUGAGAGAGCGCGCCCAGCCGCCGCAGUCGUCACUCCCCGGCUUUUCCCGCAGCUCUUUCCCCCUCUCUAAGGCAGCGACAACUUCACGUGGACAGGAUGGAAGUUUUGCGCGGAAGCCGGGAACGGCCGGAGCGUGCGCCGCGCUGCCGGCAGCCUCGCACUUGCGCAGGGAGGUGGGGCGGGGGCGACGUCGCCACCGGCUACUGCGGGCUCGUGAGGCCGCCGGGGGCCUCGGGGGAGGCCGCCAGGGACGCGGGGGGCGGCGGCGCGCGGGGGACCCACUCCGUUUUUAUUUGACCUCGGGUGACUGCCUAUUGUCAUGGUUUGCGAUCUCGCGUGGGGACCGCCCAGGGCCUCGGGGCCCUGGAUGUCCCGGGUGGCGCCGCCGUAAUCUCCGUGCCCUCCGCGCCGCCCCCACCCCGCCCCCACCCGGGCCGACUCGAGCGGCUGCAGCCUCCAGGCUGAGGGGAGGGACCCGCGACCGCGCUCUCCUCCCUGGGCCGGAGAGCCACUGUCGAUCCCCACCUGCUUCUGUGGGGCAGCCCCCGGAAUUGCCUGGAACUCUCUCGCUACCCAGUUCCCCUGUGCAGGCCACUGCGGGCCCCCUGCCGGACUCCUUUCCACUUACCCCAAGGGAGGAGACAGAAGGGACUUCGCCUACUUGCAACAACGUGAAAUAAAAACCAACCCAGACCAGACUGGGGCGCUUUUUCUGACGGGAGGAAAUACCCUUUUCCGUGGAGAUAUAUGUUAUGAAGGACUAAGCGGUCUGGGGAUAGGCUGUGCUGCGAAGGGCCUGGGCCCCUUCCAGUGCUGCUGGGUGCAGGUAUAGGCAUCCGUCCCAGACGCCCAAAGGUCAGGCAGCAACGACUUACUUCCAAGGCGGCGUCAGAGCUUCUCUAGGCACAUUGCUGAAAUGACAUUUCGUGUCUAAGCCUUCUGCGCAUGCACUACGCGACUACAUAGGAUUUACGAUUUUAUACCCACACGUGUGUAUGCCACAACCAGGGGACACAGCAAAGGUAGACGGAAUAAACAAUCCAUAAAUUUUGCAUCCAUUUAAUCACCUCUUCCAAAAACCUAUUGUCUAUUUUAGCGGCACCUUCUCUGUCAUAUUGAUAAUAAAUGUUUUAAUUUAUUGAUAAA